GUCAUUUCCUCCAGCUAGAGGAGCUCAACUGAUCUGUUUUCUUUCGCCCAGCCAAAAUCACAGAAUGAAGGCGGUGAAGAGCGAACGGGAGCGAGGGAGCCGGCGAAGACACCGGGACGGGGACGUGGUGCUGCCGGCGGGGGUGGUGGUGAAGCAGGAGCGUCUCAGCCCAGAAGUCGCACCUCCCGCCCACCGCCGUCCGGACCACUCCGGUGGUAGCCCGUCUCCGCCGACCAGCGAGCCGGCCCGCUCGGGCCACCGCGGGAACCGAGCCCGAGGAGUUAGCCGGUCCCCACCCAAAAAGAAAAACAAGGCCUCAGGGAGAAGAAGCAAGUCUCCUCGCAGUAAGAGAAACCGAAGUCCUCACCACUCAACAGUCAAAGUGAAGCAGGAGCGUGAGGAUCAUCCCCGGAGAGGACGGGAGGAUCGGCAGCACAGGGAACCAUCAGAACAGGAACACAGGAGAGCUAGGAACAGUGACCGGGACAGACACCGGGGCCAUUCCCACCAAAGGAGAACGUCUAACGAGAGGCCUGGGAGUGGGCAGGGUCAGGGACGGGAUCGAGACACUCAGAACCUGCAGGCUCAGGAAGAAGAGCGGGAGUUUUAUAAUGCCAGGCGACGGGAGCAUCGCCAGAGGAAUGACGUUGGUGGUGGCGGCAGUGAGUCUCAGGAGUUGGUUCCUCGGCCUGGUGGCAACAACAAAGAAAAAGAGGUGCCCGCUAAAGAAAAACCAAGCUUUGAACUUUCUGGGGCACUUCUUGAGGACACCAACACUUUCCGGGGUGUAGUCAUUAAAUAUAGUGAGCCCCCAGAAGCACGUAUCCCCAAAAAACGGUGGCGUCUCUACCCAUUUAAAAAUGAUGAGGUGCUUCCAGUCAUGUACAUACAUCGACAGAGUGCGUACCUACUGGGUCGACACCGCCGCAUUGCAGACAUUCCAAUUGAUCACCCGUCUUGUUCAAAGCAGCAUGCGGUCUUUCAAUAUCGGCUUGUGGAAUAUACCCGUGCUGAUGGCACAGUUGGCCGAAGAGUGAAGCCCUACAUCAUUGACCUUGGCUCAGGCAAUGGAACCUUCUUAAACAACAAACGUAUUGAGCCACAGAGAUACUAUGAACUAAAAGAAAAGGAUGUACUCAAAUUUGGAUUCAGUAGCAGAGAAUACGUCUUGCUCCAUGAGUCGUCGGACACUUCUGAAAUAGACAGGAAAGAUGACGAGGAUGAGGAGGAGGAGGAAGAAGUGUCUGACAGCUAGCAAACUAAGAACCCAAACUAUUGAUACACGGUUUCCUUCUUGGAAGUCUUUGAUUGACUCAGAGAGCACUAUGGUGGUGGGUCCAGCACUAUGGUGCUCUCUGUAAUGCCUCUUACUGCCUUAAGUCUUUCCUCUGUUGCUGACCAGAUUGUGUUACCAUUUGAAUACACUGACUAAUGUUUGUUAAACUUUUUCUGUGGCACCUUGGCCACAUGCCUGCAGGCAUUUGUUUUCAGAACAGUCUCACCAAUUACAACACACCGUGUUUUAGUAGAAGUGUUGUGGUUUUAGUUGGUGCUUUCAGAACUGCUGCCUAGGAAACUAUAAACCCUUGGUUAAGGGGAAAUCAUGGCUUGUUCUCUUUGUACAGUUACUUUAUUUAUAUAGGUGUUAAGCUUUGUGGACCAGGUGUUUUUCUUUUGGGGCGAACCCCUGAGCAGAGAAUCUUACUAGGCUUUGGUUAUCACCAAAACAACCUCCAGUAUAUACCAAAGCUUUGACUUGUUUGAGCUCUUGAGCUUAGAAGUUGAUUUUGCACUUAUUUUUUUGGGGGGUGGGAAUGUACUGCAGUCAGUAAACAUUAUUGACUGUUUAACUUAAACAGAUGCUUUAUGGCACCUGCUCAAGCCCGUGACUGUACAGAAGGAUCCUGGUUGCUACCAGUGGGUGCUGAUUCAGCAUCACAAGUGACUGAAAUUGGCUGUGGAUCUGUUCUUUGUGAAAGAAUUCCUGAUUUCUCCAUGGAGCAUGUACACAACAAUUUUGAUCAUAUUAACUGUACUUCAGUUUUGCAUUUUUAUUCAAAUGUUAUCUCUUUUUUUCUUUGAGAAAUAAACUGUCACUGAUGUGACAGCGUUCUUUCUUUAUUCUAAUAACAUGUAUAGAUCUAAAGCAGGUUGUGUUGUUUACAUGUUUCUACACAUUUCAUCCUUUAAAAAGUUGUUGAGAGAGGUUGUAUUUACCUUCCCAAGGUUGGAAAGCAGGGGAAUUUCCCAGUGUCCUAGUUUUCCACCAGAGGAAUAUGUGUAAGUAGCAAAGUAUUUGCUGCUUACAUAUAGUGUGUAUGUAUGUAUAUAUGUAAAUUGUGUGUUAAAGAGCUGAUACUGAUUUUCAUAUGACAAUGUUAGGCAAAGGCCUCCCUGCAUUUGAAGAGCAGGUUUUCAUUUAUAUGUAUUUUUGGGAUAAAAAAAUAAAAUUUGUAAAUAUAGCCCCAUUUCAAAGAGUAAUGCUUUCCUAGCGUAGAGGACCUUGUGUUCAUAGGUCUGUUUGCUGCUAAUGGAGCCUUCUGUCAGUACUUUUGAGAUAAAAGUAGGUAGCUGUUUUAGAGUGUUGUGGGGCAGGUUAUAUCGUUGGCCUCCAAGUCAGUGGAAUAGCAGAUGGUGACAUGGAGGUGGGUUGUGGGGAAAGGUGGUGAAGCAGCUCAAUCAGUGUUACUACUAAUUGUUCCUCUUGGGUUGAGACUUAGGAUACUAUUAAAUUUGAUUGUUUUCCAUUGUUUUUAUACCCAUGUGUGCUCAGGGCUAAAGAUUGGCUAGUGGGAGGGGCAGCUGACUAAUGUUCAUUCAGAAGAAGUUAAAAGAUCCUUUGAAAAGUGAACACUUAAUAAGGUCAUUAGAUGAAACGUAAGUUGGGCCGGGCAUGGGCACAGUGGCUCAUGCCUGUAAUCCCAACACUUUCGGAGGCUGAGGUGGGCAGAUCAUCUGAGGUCAGGAGUUCAAGACCAACCUGGCCAACAUGGUGAAACCCCAUCUCUACUAAAAAUACAAAAAUUAGCUGGGCGUGGUGGCACAUGCCUGUUUUAAUCCCAGCUACUCGGGAGGCUGAGGCAGGAGAAUCGCUUGAACCCGGGAGGUGGAGGUUGCAGCGAGCUGAGAUUGUGCCACUGCACUCCAGCCUGGGUGACAGCGAGACUCUGUCUCAGAAAAAAAAAAAAAAGGUAAGUUGAAGAAUGUGUUCUACAUUGGCCACUGUAACUGCUAUUUUCUUCAUUUUGGUAUGUGCCAUAGAUCAUAUAUAUGUGCUUGUCUGAAAAGUAGGUUUGUUUGGAUGAACUUUUCUCUUGAUCCAGACUGACGGUUUUCUCUUGAGGGUUUAAGCACUAAUCUGGUAUCUUACUCUAGGAUCUCCUUGUUCAGUCUGUGCUGCAGUAGCACUACUUUGUGGUAGCCUUGAGUUUUGCUACAAACUUCAUCCUGGUGGGCACUGUGAUAGAUGACCACUUUGCCUACAUUUUUCAGUAAGAAGUCCUAAUUGUUUAGUCAGUUUUUAUUUUAGUAGAGGAAUAACGUCCUGGAUUAAGAAAUUCUUUAUGCCACAUAUCUGAGAAGGUGGGUUUUUUUGUUGGUUUGUUUGUUUUGAGAUGGCGUCUCACUCUGUCGCCCAGGCUGGAGUGCAGUGGCACCAUCUUGGCUCACUGCAACCUCCGCCUCCCAGUUUCAAGCGAUUCUCCUGCCUCAGCCUCCCAAGUAGCUGGGACUACAGGCACCUGUCACCAAGCCUGGCUAAUUUAUAUAUAUAAUUUUUAUUUUUUAUUUUUUUUUAGUAGAGAUGGGGUUUCACCAUAUUGGCCAGGCUGGUCUCGAACUCCUGACCUUGUGAUCCGCCCCUCUCAGCCUCCCAAAGUGCUGGGAUUACAGGUGUUAGCCACCAGGCCUGGCCUGAGAAGGUGUUUUUUUUUUUUUUUGGUCUUGUUUUCCCUUACCCCUUUCUUUGAAGAAAGGGUGUCAAAAGACAUUACCUGCCUCUAAAGCCAGAUAUCACCAGCAGACUUCUUAAAGUGGACAUAAUCCUAGAGCUUUCAUUCUGUUUAGAAGUUCAUGUUCAUCUUAGCCAUUUGGAACUUCUUCAUUCUCUAUCUUUUCUCCACGGUGGCUGGGCUUGUCUGCAAAUCAUUGUGUCAAAAUCAAACUAUUUUCAAAACAGCCCUUUGCUUCUGAGCCCCUCCCCUAAGUCCUCUGUGGGGGUCCAUGAUUCUGCAGAGGUAUGGGACAGAAUCUUCAGAUUUUACCCCUUGAGUCUCUUCCUAGUCAUAUCCUGGUUCCCUCAUUCUAAUAUUGACAAAGGAUGACUCAUUAAGUGCAACUGGUUAUGUAACUUUCAAAUACUUUCAUUGUGUAUGUCAGGAUCUGAGGAACAAAAUGAUGUCAUUUAAUCGGAAUCUAAACGUGACACAAACAACGUGCCAGCAAUACCUGCUUGUGAAAUAAUGUUCUGAGCCCACAGUGUUCCUGGGUAUGUGAGUUUAUAUCAAGUGAAAAGGCUGCUUAAUUGACAUUAAAGUUUUGGAAUGUAAAGCUUCA